AUCGGCGGCCCGGAACCGGCCUUGGAACAACUGUGGAACCUGAGGCCGCUUGCCCUCCCGCCCCAUGGAGCGGCCCCCGGGGCUGCGGCCGGGCGCGGGCGGGCCCUGGGAGAUGCGGGAGCGGCUGGGCACCGGCGGCUUCGGGAACGUCUGUCUGUACCAGCAUCGGGAACUUGAUCUCAAAAUAGCAAUUAAGUCUUGUCGCCUAGAGCUAAGUACCAAAAACAGAGAACGAUGGUGCCAUGAAAUCCAGAUUAUGAAGAAGUUGAACCAUGCCAAUGUUGUAAAGGCCUGUGAUGUUCCUGAAGAAUUGAAUAUUUUGAUUCAUGAUGUGCCUCUUCUAGCAAUGGAAUACUGUUCUGGAGGAGAUCUCCGAAAGCUGCUCAACAAACCAGAAAAUUGUUGUGGACUUAAAGAAAGCCAGAUACUUUCUUUACUAAGUGAUAUAGGGUCUGGGAUUCGAUAUUUGCAUGAAAACAAAAUUAUACAUCGAGAUCUAAAACCUGAAAACAUAGUUCUUCAGGAUGUUGGUGGAAAGAUAAUACAUAAAAUAAUUGAUCUGGGAUAUGCCAAAGAUGUUGAUCAAGGAAGUCUGUGUACAUCUUUUGUGGGAACACUGCAGUAUCUGGCCCCAGAGCUCUUUGAGAAUAAGCCUUACACAGCCACUGUUGAUUAUUGGAGCUUUGGGACCAUGGUAUUUGAAUGUAUUGCUGGAUAUAGGCCUUUUUUGCAUCAUCUGCAGCCAUUUACCUGGCAUGAGAAGAUUAAGAAGAAGGAUCCAAAGUGUAUAUUUGCAUGUGAAGAGAUGUCAGGAGAAGUUCGGUUUAGUAGCCAUUUACCUCAACCAAAUAGCCUUUGUAGUUUAGUAGUAGAACCCAUGGAAAACUGGCUACAGUUGAUGUUGAAUUGGGACCCUCAGCAGAGAGGAGGACCUGUUGACCUUACUUUGAAGCAGCCAAGAUGUUUUGUAUUAAUGGAUCACAUUUUGAAUUUGAAGAUAGUACACAUCCUAAAUAUGACUUCUGCAAAGAUAAUUUCUUUUCUGUUACCACCUGAUGAAAGUCUUCAUUCACUACAGUCUCGUAUUGAGCGUGAAACUGGAAUAAAUACUGGUUCUCAAGAACUUCUUUCAGAGACAGGAAUUUCUCUGGAUCCUCGGAAACCAGCCUCUCAAUGUGUUCUAGAUGGAGUUAGAGGCUGUGAUAGCUAUAUGGUUUAUUUGUUUGAUAAAAGUAAAACUGUAUAUGAAGGGCCAUUUGCUUCCAGAAGUUUAUCUGAUUGUGUAAAUUAUAUUGUACAGGACAGCAAAAUACAGCUUCCAAUUAUACAGCUGCGUAAAGUGUGGGCUGAAGCAGUGCACUAUGUGUCUGGACUAAAAGAAGACUAUAGCAGGCUCUUUCAGGGACAAAGGGCAGCAAUGUUAAGUCUUCUUAGAUAUAAUGCUAACUUAACAAAAAUGAAGAACACUUUGAUCUCAGCAUCACAACAACUGAAAGCUAAAUUGGAGUUUUUUCACAAAAGCAUUCAGCUUGACUUGGAGAGAUACAGCGAGCAGAUGACGUAUGGGAUAUCUUCAGAAAAAAUGCUAAAAGCAUGGAAAGAAAUGGAAGAAAAGGCCAUCCACUAUGCUGAGGUUGGUGUCAUUGGAUACCUGGAGGAUCAGAUUAUGUCUUUGCAUGCUGAAAUCAUGGAGCUACAGAAGAGCCCCUAUGGAAGACGUCAGGGAGACUUGAUGGAAUCUCUGGAACAGCGUGCCAUUGAUCUAUAUAAGCAGUUAAAACACAGACCUUCAGUUGAACAUCUGCUAAAUACUGAGCAAGGUCUGCUGGAAAGAGUACUGGAUGGGGAAUCAGAGGCUUGAAUUCUAGAUUGAGUAAUUUACUGACCGUUACCUCAGGCAAAUCUGCGUUUCCCAUUUCCUUCUUCUGCAAAAUGGGGUUGAAACCUAGCUUUCCUACUCAGUGAGUAUAUUGUGACAGUGUAUUUAAGAGGAUGUUUGUGAAAAUGCUUUGAAAACUAUAAACUAUUAUGUACUUGCAAGAUAUUAUCAUUUAGUUAAAAAUUUGUUUUGAAGGGUAACAGAAGAAAUAAAGUCUGUGCCCUAAUGUGCAUUAUACUUAAAUGCAUGUUAAAAAAAGAUAUACUUUUACACUUUAAAAUUUGUAGACACAUAGCAACACAUGCAAAUUAAUAUACAUGUGAAAUUGUAUUUCAUAUACUAUUUUCACAUUUAAAAAAUAACAUUAUCUCCUCUUAUACUGCUUUUAUUUUACUGAAAUGUAUUCAGUUUAGUCUGACCAGCAGUUCUCAAAAUGUGGCAUAUGGACCUGUGAGAAUCCUUGAAACUUUGUCAGAGAGUCUGUGAGGUUAGAACCAUUUUCAUAAUAAGAUGUUAUUUGCAUUUUUCACCAUGUUGACAUUUUCAUUGAUGGUGCAACAUAAAAUGGCUUUCACCUUAGUAUGAAUCAAGGCACUAGCGCCAAACUAUGCUAGUAGCCGUUAUAUUUUUUACCACCAUGCAGUCACAGUUUUUAAAAAAUGACAGUUUCACUUACAAAUGUCCUUGAUAAAGCAGUAAAAAUAUUAUUUUAUUUAAAUCUCAACGCUUGAGUAUGGGUUUUUAAUAUUUUGUGUGAUGAAAUGGGAAGUACUCAUAAAGUGUUUCUUCUAUACAGUGAAGUAUGAUGGUUGUCUUAAGGAAAACCACUUCAGUAAUUGUUUACGUUGCUAGUUGUCUGGCCUCUUUCAGGGAAGAUACCAUUUUUACUUGGAAGAGCAACUGUCAGGCAAACUAUGAUUAUUCAGAUUUGCAUACGUGAGAUAAUUUCUAAGAAAUUAAAUGAAAAUAAAAAGUAUAGCACACUUAUUACUUUAAGGGAAAAAAGCAGUAUUUGUUGUCAAUGAUAAAAUUCCAUGUUUCAAGCAAAAAGAAUUUUAGAAAACUUGUAUUUACCAGCUGGAAUGACAGCUUCUCAGUACUUAAAAACUUUUCUGAUGAGAUUAGUGGUGAUAUCAGAAAGGUUUGCAAAAAUGUAAAACAGUGCAAGUGUUCUCACUCAAAUUUUUUUGUUUUAGAAAAUAUCGUUUUUUGGUUUUUGUUUUUAGAGGUGGGCUCUUGCUAUGUUGACCAGGCUGGCCUUGGACUCCCUGGGUUCAAGUGAUCCUUCCACUUCAGGCUUCCAAGUAUCUCAAGUAGCAGUAACCAGUGAAAGGAGGUGGCUCUCGUAGAUAUGAGUAUACUGUGUAGACACAUGUAUGUAUAGCACUUAGCAUGUCUGAGGAAAUGCAGUAUGACUGGAGUGUAGAGUUUCAGGAGAGAGAAAACCUAAAUAUAGGAGAGAGAGAAAACGUAAAUAUAGGUUUUUUUGUUUGUUUUUAAUAAAAACAUGUUAAUGGGCAAUAGGUUUGUUAUUUUUAAAUGAAUUAAGACACGAGUAUUUUUAAAUUUCUGUUUAAUUCCUGAAAAACCCUUUGGGGUUCUCAAGAAUUUUCUAGUGUAAAGGGGUCCUGAGACCAAAAAGUUUGAGAACUGCUUAUCUAGACUAUUCUCAGAAGCUUGGCUGCUCAGGAAAGAAGAGAGGUGGGUGAGUAGCUAAAAGUUGAUGUAGAGUCAAGGGAGGUCACUUCUCAGAAGGAAGACUUAAACAUGAGGUGCCACAUGAUGAUGUUUUGGUUAACAACAAAUUGUGUAUACUAUGGUAGUCCCAUAAGAUUAUACUACUGUAUUUUUACUAUGUAUUUUCUAUGUUUACAUGCACAAAUACUUACCAUUGUGUUACAGUUGCCUACAGUAUUCAGUACAGUCACUUGCUGAACAGGUAUGUAGCCUAUUGUCAAAAGGCUAUACCAUACAGCUUAAGUGUAUAGCAGGCUGUACCAUCAGGGUUUGUAUAAGUAUUCACACAGUGACGAAAGUGCCCAAUGAUGCACUUCUCAGAACAUAUGCUCAGGGCCAAAAAAGCCUGUGGAGAGGGAGGUCCCUGAACAAGUUGAGAGAUUGGCUCCAAAGAACAGUAGGAGGGAUUAGCCUUGAUACUAUUGAUAUUGGAAAGAGAAUGAGUGUGGAUACAGAUACUUUUUUGGGAGUAGAGGUUGGAAGAUCAGGGUCUUACUGCCUUAUGGCCUCUUAUCCUGCAGUGGUAAGUGAGGUUAACUGAAAUGGAAGAGGUGACGACCUCAUAGAUUUGAAUAGAGUGCUAAAGACUUCUAAAAGCCACUGUGUGCAGUGGAAGAUGUUGUUGACCCAAAACAUUCAUUAAGAAUCCAGGCCAGGUGGCUCAUACCUGUGAUACUAGCGCUUUGGGAGGCUGAGACAGGAGGAUCGUUUGAGGCCAACAGUUUGAGACCAGUCUGGGCAACAUAGUGAGACCCUGUCUCUACAAAAAAAUAAAUCAAUAAAAUUUUUAAAAAGCUGGGUGUGGUAGUGUAUGCCUGUAGUCCCAGCUACUCAGGAGGCUGAAGUAGCAGGAUCGCUUGAGGCCCAGGAGGUCGAGGCUGCAGUGAGCCAAGAUUACACUACUGCACUUCAGCCUGGGUUGACAGAGCAAGACUUUCUUAAAAAAAAAAAAAAAAAAAACCCAGAGCAGAAAUGAAAAACCUGUGAAUUAGCAGUGACAAAUAGUGAACAGUAAUAUUAAUUUUUUGUUGAUAAUUUAGUAGCUUGGAUACAGGAACUGAUAGAGCAGAUGGUUGGAUUAAUCCAAGGUUAGGAUUUUGCUGAUGGAAUAAGAGGAUAAAAAGGUUGAAGAUGUUAACAAAUAGUGAUUUAAGUGAUAGAAGUUGUAGCUAGAGUAAAAUAUUAAAAUCUAAGAUUUCAAAUAGAGCAAGUCCAAUUCUUUUUCUUUAAUCAAUAUUUCUGGGCCAGGCGUCGUGGCACAUGCCUGUAAUCCCAGCCACUUUGGAGGCUGAGGCAGGAGAAUUGCUUGAACCAGGGAGGCAGAGGUUGCAGUGAACCAAGACUGUGCCACUGCACUCUAGCCUGGGUGACAGAGCUAGACUCCAUUUCAAAAAAAAAAUUCUGACUCCCAGUUUUCUGGCUAAUGAAUCAGAUACCACAGAUACACAGUGAUAGCAUUUGUUUAGGUUAUAUUUUUUAAAACUUUGAGGCAGCCCUGUCAACAUACCAUGAAGCUCAGAAAUAAACUGCUACCCAGGUAGCUUCUUUGAGUGUCACCUUGAGUGACAAACUGUAACAAGAUUGUGUCUGUCAUUGGGGCCUAUUAUAUAAUCACACUUGAUUUGUGGCCUCUAUUGUCUUUUCUAGCUUAGAGUUGACUUGAAUCUCUUGUUCAUCUGAAAUGGUUAAAACCAGCUUUCUUCAUUAUCCUGGAGAAGGCUAAAGUUCUGAGGGCUUUCACUGUCUUAAGGAGCUAGUUAUAUGAGAAAGCUCUUGGCUUGGUCCAUGGUAUUUAGGAAGGAAUGCUGUUUGGAGAAGAACCUUUUUGGAGCCUUGCAUUUGAUUGUUGGUGAGGAGGAGACAACAGAGAUGUGUGGGGAAUAAAGUUGGGCUAUGGGGGAAGUAUUUGGAGUGAUAGAUAACAAAGGACACAACGUUUUUUAAACCUCCUUUGAUGCUCAUCAUUUCCUUUUUGGUAAAAUGGGGGUAACAAAAGUAGUCUUCUCACAUGACUGCUGUGAGGAUUAAAUGGGAAAAUUAUAAGCAGAGAGUAGCAAAUAUUAUUAUUAUUGCAUUUAGGCUUAAUUAUUGUCCAAAGAAUAUACCAGCAUGAUGCAUAAGCAACUUUCAACUCCUUUAGCCAUUUUCUGAAAUAUAACAAUUAAUGAUUUUUUUUUAAAAUCGAGGUCACAUUUUAAACUGUAGAACCCAUUGUGACCAACAGCCAUCCCAUUUGAGGGUAUCUGGCUGCUGCCAGUUGGCUUUAAGAUGUCAUACUGCCCUCAAAUGGAACUUUCAGGAUGUCUACAGGUCCCUUUACUAGUUGGUUUCAAUGAGCUUUUUUCAAAGUUUUUCUGGGUUGUAAACAGACGGAUAAACAUGAAAUUCCAAGCAACCUAGUUCAAGGGCCUCCUUCCUUUAGGUAAUGAAAGUUUGAUGAAUUGUCCUACUGUUUCUAAAUAUGUGGUUAAUCAUCCAAGAAAAAUUGUUCCCUUGGCCAGAGGCUGCAUUUGUGUCUAGGGCUUGGGUUAGUAUGGGUUAAAGAUAGCCAAGACUAUUGUUCUCAAGCACAGGCAACUAAGGUCUCUUACUGAUAAAUUUAUAUAUACAUUAUACACCUGCAAACUUUAUUUUUUAUAUAUAACUAGAUUUUAUUUAUAGGUAAUCUUUAUAUCUUUUAUCUUAACCCAAUUUUUAAUUUAAAUGGAGAUGUUUAUUAAUUAAAAUUAGUUUCAGAGUUUCAGGGAUUUUUGAGGAAUUUUUUGUUUGGAGGCUGAUAUGUUACAGAAGAAAGGUUAUAUCCACUGACUGAU